GUCCGGCGGCAGCGGCGUUGGGGACUCCGGCGGGGGAUGCGCGCCCGGCCCCUCAGCGCCCCCAGCACGCCGCCGAGUCCCGCUCGCCAUGGGUAAGUCCCGAUCGGGCGCUGCCUGCUGGAAGCCCGACCCCUUCCCAGGGUGUAGACACCGCCCCCACGCUCCCCUAAGAGUGCGCGCCCCCUGGCUCCCCCAGGGCCGCCCCGGCCGGAUACCGCCUCUCGGGUGGCCAGCCCGAGACUGCAGGCCUGCGGCGGGGGCUGGGACGGGGCUCGGUCGCGCUUCCUUCCAUCUUCCUUUCUGCCCCGGAAAAGUGGCCCCUCACUUGCUGCAGCGCCCACUCGGGCCCAGGCACUCUCCCGGGCGCCCUGAUCCGACAGCCCCAGGCAAGUGCAGCUGUUCCUGGUCUGCAGAUGAAGAAAUGGAGGCUCCGAAAGAAGCAAAGCAGUUCAUCGAUUCGCUGAGCGCGGUUGUGCCCCAGGCGCUGUUGUGGGCCUGGGGACGCUGUCGCGAACGAAACUGCGAACAAAACAGACGAACCCCCUCCUCUGGACGUGAUUCUGCAGAGAGGGGACAGAGAAGGAGAUUCUAACACAGCAUUGGGGUGGGACGCGUGGGGAAUGGCUUUGUUGCCACUCGGGACUAGGGCUCUAUUUUUCUCUCUGCAUUCAGAAGCCUCGAAGGAUCAGUCGUUGAUUCUUGAGUGAGCACCUACUACGUGCCAGACAUUGAUAUAGGGGUUAGAGCUUCAGCAAUGAACAAAAUAGACAAUAAACCUCUCUCUCAUGGAGGUGGCAUUCUGAUUGAGCAGCUGGGUAAACACGUUUAUGAAUAACUUCAGAGAGAGAUAAGGUGUUGUGGAACCCAUAAAAUGGGGUGGCGUGAAGGCCAAGGGCGUGGGUUCCUUGGGUAGGUGGUCAGGGUGGGUUUUCUGGAGUAGGACGUUUUGGAGCUGAGAACUUCCUCAGAAGCGGGUCUUGCUGAGAUCUGGAGAAAGAGCUUCCAGGUGGCAGCAACAGUGCAAAGGCCCUCAGGCAGGAAUGAGUUUGUGUGGCCCAGGCCAGGAUGGCCAGAGCACAGCGGGCAGGGCACUGAGGUCAAAGGGAUGGCAGAGAGGUGUGCAGGGCUUUGUAAGCCGUGGUGAGAAGUUCAGAUUUUAUUGCAAAUGCCACGGCAAGCUGGAGAAGGGUUUUAAGCUGGAGCGGGGCCGUGACCUGAAUUAUCUUUUCUUUUUUUUUUCUUUUUUUUGAGAUGAUCACUCUGUCGCCAGGCUGGAGUGCAGUGGCGUGAUCCCGCUCACUGCAACCUCCAGCUCCCUGGUUCAAGCAAUUCUCCUGCCUCAGCCUCCCAAGUAGCUGGGAUUACAGGCAUACACCACCACGCCCAGCUAAUUUUUGUAUUUUUAGUAGAGAGUGGGUUUCACCAUGUUGGCCAGGAUGUCUUGAUCUCCUGACCUCGUGAUCCGGCUGCCUCGGCUUGGGAUUACAGGCGUGAGCCUCCGCGCCCGGCCCUGAAUUAACUUCUCAAAGUUUGCUCUGAGUCGUUCUGUGGAGAAUCACAGUCGCUAACACUGGCUAUGAUGUAGGUAAGCAUAGAAGGUAGGCAUUAAUAUCCCAUUUGUAGAUGGGGAAGCCCAGAGAGGUGAGGUGAGUUCCCCAAGGUCACACAGCUAUGGAGAGGAGAAGCUGGGAAGGAGCCCCAGCAUUCUGACUCCAGUCUGCAUUCCUAACCACUGCACCACGUGGCCUGUCAUGGUGGAUUAAUGGUAAAACUGGUGACCAGUUCCGGCUCUGACAGGAGAGUCCAUCCUCUUAACCCCCACAGCACAGUGCCCCAGAGCCUGAGAAAAAAAUGAGGCCCAGAGAGGUCAAGGUCUUCUUAAGGACACUCAGCUUAGCCCUAGCCCCUUGUUCCUGCACCUCCUAUUCCUGCUAAAUCAACCCAACAGCCAUUUGCUGAGUGCCUUCUAUGGGCAGAGCGAGGGCUGGGUGUUAGUGCUGGGGGAGGCAUAAGUCAUGGCUGCGGGUCUCUGUCCUCCCCAGAAUUCUUACACAGCAGGGACCAGGGAUUGGGCUCUCUUUAUAGCCUCUGGGGGCAGAACUGGGUUCUAGACCCAAUUCCUCUCACUUUGUUCCACCAUUCCACUUUGACCUGGGAGAGUCUGCCAACUUCUCUGGUCACUAUCAAAUACCCUUAUCACAGGGUAGCCAUGAGAAUGAUGUGAAAAAAUGAAUUACAGUGCUCGGCUCAUCACCUAUAUCUGGUAAAUGGUGAGUGAAUGUGAGUUUUUAUUUUAUAUUGCACCCAAUAUUGGGAUUCUGGAGUCAGACUGCCCGAGUUCAAGUUCCUGCUAUGUGACUUACAAACUGUGCCACCUUGGGGAAAUGUCUUCACCUCUCAGUGUGGUGGUUAUUUCUGUAAAAUGGGAAUGACAAUAGUGAUUGUCAUAGGAUUGUCUAGGGAUUAAGCCAGCUGGUACAGAUACUGCCCCUUAGGAGAGUGGCUGGCUAUAGUGGGUACUCCAAGUAUCAGCUGUGGCUGCAAUUGCUGGGACAUUUGGAAGCCGGCCAUCUGCAAGAGGAUAUUCAUACAGUUCAAUUUCACAUCUGGCUUCUCCCUGGAGCUUCAGGGAAAGCCACAGCAGGUCUCUGGUGCAGGAGGGACCCAGUGCUCUGUGACCUCUGGUUGAGACACUACUCUAGUGUCACCAACGGGAGGCCUAGGACUUGCAGCUGGAGAUACUUGCAUCCCAAACCAGGGUUCUCCCCCCUCCCCCUGCCCCCUGACCCUGUCCCGGGGAAGCUGUGCCCUCCACAGCGAGGGGCUUAGAGGAUUAAGGGAUUUCCUCCAGUGUGGGACAUCUUCACUACAGCCUAUGUUAGGCAGGUUAUUAAUAGAAAGGAUGCACACUUGCUAAACUUAGGUCAAGCCGUCUUAAUGUGUUCUCCUUAAUUUUCUUUCUUUUCUUUUUUUCUCUUUCUUUCUUUCUGUCUUCUUUCUUUCUUUUUUUUUUUUUUUUUUUUUUGACAAAGUCUGGCUCUGUCAUCUAGGCUAGAGUGCAGUGGUACAGUCUCGGCUCACUGCAACCUCUGCCUCCCAGGCUCAAGCCAUCCUCCCACCUCAGCCUCCCAAGUAGCUGGAAUUACAGGUGCACACCACUAUUCCUGGCUCAUUUUUGUAUUUUUUGGUAGAGAUGGGGUUUCACCGUGUUACCCAGGCUGAUCUUGAACUCAUGAACUCAAGUGAUCCACUUGCCUUAGCCUCCCAAAGUAUUGGGAUUAUAGGCAUGAGCCACCGAGCCCAGCCUAAGACAUCUUAAUUUGAGGACGAGGCUUUGCUCUGCUUCCUGUCCAUGGCCACUUCCAGGCCCUGGACCUUUCAGAUGUUCAUGAGCCAAGAUCCUUUCUUUCUGGAUUUCCUACAUCCCCACAGUUCAUUUGGUUUUUCAUUCAUUCACUCAAUCAUUCAUUUGUUUAACAAAUAUUAUUGAUUGAGUGCUGAGUAACUGUCCUUGGCCUCAGGGAGACAGCUGAGAAGAAACAAACCACUCCUGUUCCCUUGAGGCUGACUUUCAGGUCAGGGAGACCAAUAAAUAUGUAAAAUAUGUAGUUAUUUUGGAAGAUGAGAAGUGCCACGCAGAAAAAACAAGUGGAGAAGGGAAUACAAAGUGCUAGAUGCUACAGGGAGGUUGAAUUUUAGGUAGAAGGCCAGGGACAGCCUCACCGAGAAGGGGAUGUUUCAGCAAAGAUCAGAAGGGAGGAAGGAAGGAACUGUUGGCAUGGAGGGACAGGACUUCCCAGGCAGAGAGGCUGGCAGGUACCAAGCUUUGAGUUGGGACGUGCUUGGAGUGAGAGUAGCAGCAAGGAACCAGUGUGACUGGAGCCCAGUGAGAGGGGGCAGAUCCUGCAGAGUCUUGAAGGCCACGGUGAGGACGUUGGCUUUUCUUAGACUGAAAUAGGAGCCUUGGAGGGCUCCUAGUGGAAGAGUGACGAGGCCUGACUUAGGUUUUCCCAGAAUCCUUCUGGCUGCUGUGUAGAAUUAGUUUAGGUUCAGAGGUAUCUGACACAGCCCUAGAAAUGUCAUGAGGUGAAAUAGCCCUGGUCCUCUACCCAGUCAUUUGUUCAUUCAGCAGAAACUUCACUGGGUUCCUCUUGGGUGUCAGGGCAGGGCUGGGGCCCCGGAGGCUCAGGACGAGUCAGUCUCUAUCCCUGCCCUCCUUAGUUGAAUAUGGAAGACUCAUAAAGGAACUUGCAGUGUGAAGGAAAAAGAGUACAGUGGAGAGUUGAGGAAGAUGCAUGGGAAUUGGUCAGGAACUCCCUCAAACUUUUCCACUGAAAGGCACUAAGCAAACAUCACUGUCUGCUGAUAGGAAGGGUACUUGGGUACUGAGAUUAAAAAAAAAAUGACAGGCCAACCUUCAGAAAAUCCAGAAAUUGGCAAUGAGUAUUUAUGGGUCACUGAAGUCUAUGGCUUCAGGUGCAGUUGGAUCUAGGGGCUCAUACAGUGUUGUCAGGAAUCCUUCAUUGGGGAAGAUGGCCCCCAGUGGCUCCAGGCAAGUAAAACACCAGCUUGGCACCCCUGGUGAGCAAACACACCCGGUCCGACUCUCACUGGCCCAGGUUCACCCACGUGGUAUUCACCUCUGCCUAGGGCCCAGGAAUUUGCUGAUUGAUUGGAUCUGGAUCAUGGACACCACCCUGGGGCUGGGCACUGAGGGUGGAGGUGGGGGCAGUCAUCUCCACCCAAACCAGGAGACUGUGAGACAAGGAAAAGGGGCGGCUCCCUGCAACGGAAGAUGAGGAGCGGAUGCCAAAUAACAGAUGUGUAUACCUGGAGGCUCCUUGGGGAGGUGGCACAGGACCUGGGACUGAAGAGGGAGAGUAGAGGAACAAGGGGACCCUUUCCUUGGGGAACAAGGACAGUGCACGUAGGAGGCCCAGCACGUGCAGUGGUGGAGCGGCAUGAAAGCAUACAGCCACUCCCCACCUGUCCUGCCUUUGUGUGCCUCUGUGUCUUUGCUGGGUGGCCUGACCUUUGGUUAUGAACUGGCAGUCAUAUCAGGUGCCCUGCUGCCACUGCAGCUUGACUUUGGGCUAAGCUGCUUGGAGCAGGAGUUCCUGGUGGGCAGCCUGCUCCUGGGGGCUCUCCUCGCCUCCCUGGUUGGUGGCUUCCUCAUUGACUGCUAUGGCAGGAAGCAAGCCAUCCUCGGGAGCAACUUGGUGCUGCUGGCAGGCAGCCUGACCCUGGGCCUGGCUGGUUCCCUGGCCUGGCUGGUCCUGGGCCGCGCUGUGGUUGGCUUCGCCAUUUCCCUCUCCUCCAUGGCUUGCUGUAUCUACGUGUCAGAGCUGGUGGGGCCACGGCAGCGGGGAGUGCUGGUGUCCCUCUAUGAGGCAGGCAUCACCGUGGGCAUCCUGCUCUCCUAUGCCCUCAACUAUGCACUGGCUGGUACCCCCUGGGGAUGGAGGCACAUGUUCGGCUGGGCCACUGCACCUGCUGUCCUGCAAUCCCUCAGCCUCCUCUUCCUCCCUGCUGGUACAGAUGAGACUGCAACACACAAGGACCUCAUCCCACUCCAGGGAGGUGAGGCCCCCAAGCUGGGCCCGGGGAGGCCACGGUACUCCUUUCUGGACCUCUUCAGGGCACGCGAUAACAUGCGAGGCCGGACCACAGUGGGCCUGGGGCUGGUGCUCUUCCAGCAACUAACAGGGCAGCCCAACGUGCUGUGCUAUGCCUCCACCAUCUUCAGCUCCGUUGGUUUCCAUGGGGGAUCCUCAGCCGUGCUGGCCUCUGUGGGGCUUGGCGCAGUGAAGGUGGCAGCUACCCUGACCGCCAUGGGGCUGGUGGACCGUGCAGGCCGCAGGGCUCUGUUGCUAGCUGGCUGUGCCCUCAUGGCCCUGUCCGUCAGUGGCAUAGGCCUCGUCAGCUUUGCCGUGCCCAUGGACUCAGGCCCAAGCUGUCUGGCUGUGCCCAAUGCCACCGGGCAGACAGGCCUCCCUGGAGACUCUGGCCUGCUGCAGGACUCCUCUCUACCUCCCAUUCCAAGGACCAAUGAGGACCAAAGGGAGCCAAUCUUGUCCACUGCUAAGAAAACCAAGCCCCAUCCCAGAUCUGGAGACCCCUCAGCCCCUCCUCGGCUGGCCCUGAGCUCUGCCCUCCCUGGGCCCCCUCUGCCCGCUCGGGGGCAUGCACUGCUGCGCUGGACCGCACUGCUGUGCCUGAUGGUCUUUGUCAGUGCCUUCUCCUUUGGGUUUGGGCCAGUGACCUGGCUUGUCCUCAGCGAGAUCUACCCUGUGGAGAUACGAGGAAGAGCCUUCGCCUUCUGCAACAGCUUCAACUGGGCGGCCAACCUCUUCAUCAGCCUCUCCUUCCUCGAUCUCAUUGGCACCAUCGGCUUGUCCUGGACCUUCCUGCUCUACGGACUGACCGCUGUCCUCGGCCUGGGCUUCAUCUAUUUAUUUGUUCCUGAAACAAAAGGCCAGUCGUUGGCAGAGAUAGACCAGCAGUUCCAGAAGAGACGGUUCACCCUGAGCUUUGGCCACAGGCAGAACUCCACUGGCAUCCCGUACAGCCGCAUCGAGAUCUCUGCGGCCUCCUGAGGAAUCCGUCUGCCUGGAAAUUCUGGAACUGUGGCUUUGGCAGACCAUCUCCAGCAUCCUGCUUCCUAGGCCCCAGAGCACAAGUUCCAGCUGGUCUUUUGGGAGUGGCCCCUGCCCCCAAAGGUGGUCUGCUUUUGCUGGGGUAAAAAGGAUGAAAGUCUGAGAAUGCCCAACUCUUCAUUUUGAGUCUCAGGCCCUGAAGGUUCCUGAGGAUCUAGCUUCAUGCCUCAGUUUCCCCAUUGACUUGCACAUCUCUGCAGUAUUUAUAAGAAGAAUAUUCUAUGAAGUCUUUGUUGCACCAUGGACUUUUCUCAAAGAAUCUCAAGGGUACCAAUCCUGGCAGGAAGUCUCUCCCGAUAUCACCCCUAAAUCCAAAUGAGGAUAUCAUCUUUUCUAAUCUCUUUUUUCAACUGGCUGGGACAUUUUCGGAAGGGGGAAGUCUCUUUUUUUACUCUUAUCAUUUUUUUUUUUUGAGGUGGAGUCUCAUUCUGUUGCCCAGGCUGGCCUGAUCUUGGCUCACUGCAACCUCCACCUCCUGAGUUCAAGCGAUUCUUGUGCCUCAGCCUCCUAAGCAGCUGGGACUACAGGCGCAUGCAACCAUACCCAGCUAAUUUAUUUUUAGCAGAGAUGGGGUUUCACUGUGUUGGCCAGGCUGGUCGUGAACUCCUGAGCUCAAGUGAUCCACCCACCUCAGCCUCCCAGAGUGCUAGGAUUACAGGCCUUUUGACUCUUUUAUCUGAGUUUUAUUGACCCCUCUAAUUCUCUUACCCAGAAUAUUUAUCCUUCACCAGCAACUCUGACUCUUUGACGGGAGGCCUCAGUUCUAGUCCUUGGUCUGCUGGUGUCAUUGCUGUAGGAAUGACCACGGGCCUCAGUUUCCCCAUUUGUAUAAUGGGAAGCCUGUACCAGGUCAUUCUUAAGAUUUCUCCUGACUCCAGUGAGCUGGAAUUCUAAAUGCUGGUCUAGGAGCUGUCUCCAGGAUGGUGCAGGAUGGCUUUGCGGAAAGGAGAUGGGUUUGGAGGCCAACAAACCUGCUUGUCAAUAUUGCCUUUGCCUCUUGGCAGCCCUUGAACUUGAGUAAAUAACAACUCCCUGAACCUCAGUUUCCUCAUCUGCAGAAUGGGGAUAAUUAUGUCCCAGGGGUAUAUUUAGACCCUGUUUCCUUUCAGGAGGGUCCCCAGCUGGUCCAGGGCCUGGGAAAUUUCUACUUAUCCUCAUUACCCAGGUCCCUCCUUUGGACCCUGUAAAGGGUCAGGGUGAAUCAGAUGGGGGACUGAGCAAGUAGCUAUGACUGCAGAUCAUGUAAGGAAGGGACUGACAAGAAGCUCCCAGAUGCUGGGGAGAAUGAAGAGCUAAAAUAGAUCCUAGGUGCUGGAUGCUUUGUCAUCCAUGCGUGCACAUAUGGGUGCUGGCAGAGCCCCCAAGGACUCUGGCCUCUCGAGUUCUCCUAUCUUCUCCAUUCUAGAUGCUUCCCUUGUAUCCAGUGAUGUGCUGGAGCUGGCUUUGCCAAGCUUGUGAGAGCUGGUUGCUACAUUUUCAGGAUUUUUACAAGUUGGUAAACACAGCCAUUAUAAAAAAUUAAAUGAUUUAAAUUUAUAAUUAAGUAAAUUACAUUAAAACAAAAAAAUUAUACUCAAAAUUCAUUACUUAAUUUUACUACCUGUUACUAUUAUCUGUGCUUUUGAGGCUAUUUCUACAUAGUAACUCUUAUGGAGACCUAGGGGAGACACCGCGCAUCUCUUCCUGAUUCCCCACUCAAUGACAUCAUGUUAGUCUUUGGUUGCUUAACUGGCUGUGGGGAGUGUUUUUGUAUCACAAAGAUUAGAGAGGACUACACAUCAGGGCUUGAUUUAUUGUUUGUUGAUUUUCUAGACUUCAGAACAUGCUGGAUAAAAUGUCAGUAAUGCAAAUUAAACUUUAAAGUAUGUCUUGUUUGUAGCCAAUACAUGGUGUAUAGCACCAAAAAAUGGAGGGAUUAUUCUUCCAGUAGUUGAACACUGUCAUCCGUUUCAGCUGACAGCUGCUCAAAUCAUUUAAGAAGGAGUUCUGACAUUCAUUUUCAUUGUUUUACUUUUGUCUUCCUCACUAGUGUAAACAAAAAUUUCAACCAGCAUUCAUGCCGAACCUAUACCCAUUCUUCAGUGCCUAGCUGUACAGUUAUCAGGGAUUUUUAUUUGUAGUCUAAUUUUGUCAAAUCAUGGCCAAAUCGCAGUGAUAGUUGACUUUGGAUACAAGGUUUGGCAAAAAAAAAAAUAUUAACAAAAUAUUCUGUAAGAAUCAAUUGUCUAUAUGGAAUUUAGGAUAAAGAAUAUUUACAAUAAAGAAUAUUUACAAUAAAGAGUUUAUUAUUAUUUGUAAGUUGUGUGCAACAAACAUACCCUUUAUCUCUGUAAAAUUUAUACACACAAAAAUUAACAAAAGAUUCUGUAAGAAUUAAUUGGCUAUAUGGAAUUUAGGAUAGAAUAUUUACAAUAAAGAGUAUUUACAAUAAAGAGUUUGUUAUUAUUUGUAAA